GCCGUGCGCCGGUUGCUAUACAGGCCGCACUUCACACCCCGUGCCUCCCCGCCUCUCCUGGCUCCUCCGCCCAGAUCCCCGGCGCUCCCGCGUUCGGUGACGGCCGGGUAGGCUGUAGGCAGCGCAAUGCCAAGACAGAGCUGCUGGCGGCGGCGGGCGAAUCUCCCUGCACCAUGAGCCUCGGCUCCGGCCCCGUUAGGGGCCGAUAAGCACAGCGCACGCCGCCCUCCAUUUGCCCCGGGGCCUCGGCUGCGAAGAUAGCGGCGGCCGGACAGGAAGCUCGAGGAAAGCGCUGGGCCGGGUCUCUACGAACACGUGAAGGAAAAGCAGCUCCGUCCACAACGCCGCUUCGGGGCUCCUAGGGAGUCGGGCCCCGGGCCGCCACCGUCACCUCGGCCGCUGCCGCUGUCGCCAUCGCCUUGUUUCCCCAUCCCCCGCCAUGGCCGAGGACCUCUCUGCGGCCACGUCCUACACCGAAGAUGAUUUCUACUGCCCCGUCUGUCAGGAGGUGCUCAAAACGCCCGUGCGGACCACGGCCUGUCAGCACGUUUUCUGUAGAAAAUGUUUCCUGACUGCAAUGAGGGAAAGCGGAGCACAUUGUCCCCUAUGUCGUGGAAAUGUGACUAGAAGAGAGAGAGCAUGUCCUGAACGGGCCUUAGACCUUGAAAAUAUAAUGAGGAAGUUUUCUGGUAGCUGCAGAUGCUGUGCAAAACAGAUUAAAUUCUAUCGCAUGAGACAUCAUUACAAAUCUUGUAAGAAGUAUCAGGAUGAAUAUGGUGUUUCUUCUAUCAUUCCAAACUUUCAGAUCUCUCAAGAUUCAGUAGGGAACAGCAAUAGGAGUGAAACAUCCACAUCUGAUAACACAGAAACUUACCAAGAGAAUACAAGUUCUUCUGGUCAUCCUACUUUUAAGUGUCCCCUGUGUCAAGAAUCAAAUUUUACCAGACAGCGUUUACUGGAUCACUGUAACAGUAAUCACCUAUUUCAGAUAGUUCCUGUGACAUGUCCUAUUUGUGUGUCUCUUCCUUGGGGAGAUCCUAGCCAGAUUACCAGAAAUUUCGUUAGUCAUCUAAAUCAGAGACAUCAAUUUGAUUAUGGAGAAUUUGUGAAUCUUCAGCUAGAUGAAGAAACCCAAUACCAAACUGCUGUUGAAGAAUCUUUUCAAGUAAACAUCUGAAGGCUGUAGACAUCUCUGCAUCUUUGUACCUGCAAGUGCCAUCUUUAAGGGGGAAACUACAUGAAGUCACCGUUACAGUAACUUGAUGUGUAUAUUAAUAAAAGUAAUUCAGUCAUUUUAGUUUUUGAUUGAAAAUAAAGGUAGGGCUUCUAAAAACUUCAUCAUCUUGAUAAGUUAAAAAAUGAAAGUUAUGACAUUAGCUUUAAAGGUGUAAAAAAGAUGUUUCACUAAUGUAACGGUGAAAGAGAAUCCCUGUUGUACUUUAUCUUUUUGUAAUAUUAUUUUUGAAUUUUUCAUUAUUAUGUUGCUUUUGAAAUUUGAUGCAUUCCUCCCAUUUACUUUAUUAUUGUACACAUUUAACACACAGUAGCAAAUUUUGAACGAUGUGAUUGAUAUAACCUAACAAAUCUGAGCCAGUUAUUAUUAGAGUUGCAGAAUAGAAACUUGAAGUGCUAAAUGGAAUAAUCCAAAGGAAAUUUUUUAAAUGCAGGUUCUAGCUGAAAAAUUCAACUAUAAGAAAAUUGUAUUUAUAUAACAUUUACUAUUUUUGAAGACUAGUGAGAUUUCUGUAAUAAUUUUAAUUCUUUAAAAAGUGAAAGCUUGUUGUAAAGAUAUUUUCUUUUUGUUAUUAGAAGGAAAUACAAAGAGAAAAAUUUCUUUCUUUCAUGGGCAUUUGAUAAUUUCAGUCUUUGACUGAUUUGUAAGCCUAGAAUAUACUAAGCUGAAUAACAGCUCUUUGGCCUCAGAAUUUUCAGUAGCCAGUAUUUCUGAUUAACUAAGUUGAAACUCUUAUUAGAAACUUUCAGUUGGUGAUAUUGUAUUCUAGAAGAUAUAAAUGAGAGGUUUGGCUUCAUCUCAGUUUAGAAAUUUAUUCAAAGCUAAAGAUGUAUAUAUACAUAUACUUUUGUGUGUAUAUAUACACAUAUGUGUGUAUGCAGUUUGUCAGGUUAUAUAUAGAAUUUCUAUUAAGGAUUUUUUAAAUGGACAAGCAAUAGGGGGUUGAAGUGUUUAUCUGAUUUGUUUAAAAUUUUGUAUAUCACCAAAUUUUUAAAAAGUGAUAGUCACAGUGCUAAGUUAUCUAGUUGGCUACUAUUACACCUUAAAAAUUGAGUUUACACACACACAAUUACCUGUUUAUAUGGUGCUCAUUUGUUAUUCUCAAAUAUAAUGUGUGACCGUGAUAUAGUGAGAAAGAUUCUACCAACCACUGUUUCACUACUUUUUAGUUAAAAUUGGGUAUGUUCUUAAUAUUCAUUAGUGAGAAUCACAAAGUAUUUUGUAGAAGGCCCAAAUCACAGAAUAAAGGACUAAGAGUGGAUUUGCUGACAUUCCAUACUAAUAUACAUUGUUUAUGCUUUCUUUAAAAUAACUAGAAGAACAUAAAAGAAAGAGAAUCUCAGAAGUAGUUUGCUGCUAAUAUAUACAUAUAUUGUAUAAAAAGGUAUAUUUUGGUUUUGUUAAAACCCUUGUUGACUUUUCUACACUGAACAUUUUUUUUAACUUGAUUUAAUAAAAAUGUUAAUUUUGGAAGUGCAGUUUUGUAAAAACCUUUUUCAGUCAAACAGUAAAGACUUUAUUUAUGGAUUGUAAUAACAACCACAAGAAAAGCCAUACAUCUUAAUGAACAUACGCCUUUGUUCUGUCAUUUUAAAGAGUGGUGUUUACUAUGUGUGUGCUUGAGCAUUUUCUUUCAGUUACAUGGGUGUAAUUUAAAAAACAGCUCCUUUUUAAGACUUUUGACCAUAGUGUUUUCCAGUUUAAAGCAAUAACUUUCAUAGUUUCUUUCAAAGUUUAAUACAUCCAAUAUGUCAAGUUAAACCAUUCUGGGAUUUGCAAAGUUUAAUACAUCCAAUAUGUCAAGUUAAACCAUUCUGGGAUUUGCAAAGUUUAAUACAUCCAAUAUGUCAAGUUAAACCAUUCUGGGAUUUGGGAACUUCUUUAAAGGAAAAUUGUAGUAGAGGUCAUCUUGAUGGAAUUGUGUUUUAAAGUUUUGUGAAUGAGUUAAAUAUCAUUGAUAGUCUUGUGUGUCUCACAUAUCAGCUUUUUCAUAAGGAAAAUACUUUAUUUGCUUUUAUCUGAGAAUUUCUCAGUAUGAAAAUGAUUGUUUAAAAUUUCCCCUCUUUUUGUCAGUGCAUUGGGAAUAGGGAUAGACUUUACAGAUUUAUGGAAAUUAAAUUUAUGGGGAAAAGUUUAUUUUUAAUAUUACUUAUAGCUGAGUCAGAAUUAAAGGAGGGAAUUGUAUUGAUACUCCAAUACCUAAAUUUCACAAUACCACUUAGGAAAGCUAUUUCAACAAAUUACAGUUUUAUUGUUAAAACAGAGUCUUAUUUGAGAUGUAUUGCUUUAUUUUUCAAUUAAAAGUGGUUUUCUCCUA